GCUGUGUAGGGCGGGCUGAGGAGCCGGCGUGCGGCGCGGCGGGACGGGACGUGCGGCCCAGCGAGUUGGUCGGUCCCGGGGUCACCCGCUACGGGAAGCAGGCCUCGCCACAGACUAAGAAAAAUGGCUUUGUCAGCCCAACAGAUACCCAGAUGGUUUAACUCAGUUAAGUUGAGGAGCCUCAUUAAUGCUGCACAACUCACAAAACGUUUUACUAGACCAGCAAGAACACUGUUACAUGGCUUUUCUGCUCAGCCUCAGAUAUCCUCUGACAAUUGCUUUCUCCAGUGGGGAUUUAAGACUUACAGGACUUCCUCCUUAUGGAAUAGUUCCCAGUCUACUAGCUCAAGUAGUCAGGAGAAUAAUUCUGCCCAAAGCAGUCUGCUUCCUUCCAUGAAUGAACAGUCACAGAAGACACAAAAUAUAUCCAGCUUUGAUUCUGAGCUGUUUCUAGAAGGUAAUUCUGAACUUUCAGAAAAGUCUCCCUUUCCCUACUUUGGCCAUUUGAACAAGCUACCUGUUUACCUUCUGCUAGCCCAUUUCAGGUAAUAUUUUGUGCCAAGAAAGAAAAAGAAUAAUACCAGUUCUAUUGAUGAACUUCUAUCAUGCCUUUAUUUUACUGCCAAUUUCAGAGGAAGAGGCUAUUCAGAUUAUUGCAGACCCUCCAUUGCCACCAGCUUCAUUCACACUUCGAGACUAUGUGGAUCAUUCUGAGACUCUGCAGAAGUUGGUUCUUCUAGGCGUGGAUUUGUCCAAGAUAGAAAAACAUCCAGAAGCAGCAAACCUCCUUCUGAGACUGGAUUUUGAAAAAGACAUUAAGCAAAUGCUUCUGUUUCUUAAAGAUGUGGGUAUAGAGGAUAACCAACUGGGAGCAUUCCUGACAAAAAAUCAUGCAAUUUUCUCUGAAGACCUUGAAAAUCUGAAGACCAGGGUGGCUUAUCUGCAUUCAAAAAAUUUCAGUAAAGCAGAUGUUGCACAGAUGGUCAGAAAAGCACCAUUUUUGCUGAACUUUUCAGUGGAAAGACUGGAUAACAGAUUGGGAUUUUUUCAGAAAGAACUUGAACUUAGUGUGAAGAAGACUAGAGAUCUGGUAGUUCGUCUCCCAAGGCUGCUAACUGGAAGUCUGGAACCCGUGAAAGAAAAUAUGAAGGUUUAUCGUCUUGAACUUGGUUUUAAACAUAACGAAAUUCAACAUAUGAUCACCAGAAUCCCAAAGAUGUUAACUGCAAAUAAAAUGAAACUUACCGAGACGUUUGAUUUUGUGCACAAUGUGAUGAGCAUUCCCCACCACAUCAUUGUCAAGUUCCCACAGGUAUUUAAUACAAGGCUGUUUAAGGUCAAAGAAAGACACUUGUUUCUUACCUAUUUAGGAAGAGCACAGUAUGAUCCAGCAAAACCUAACUACAUCUCUUUGGACAAACUAGUAUCUAUUCCUGAUGAAAUAUUUUGUGAAGAGAUUGCCAAAGCAUCAGUACAGGACUUUGAAAAAUUCUUAAAAACGCUUUAGAUUUUUAUGUAUGUUAAAAUGCAGUAUUGUAAAGUGAAUAUAUAUAUGAAUAAAUGAAUAUAUUUUUAAAUGCCUCGGGUCUCAACUGAUAUU